AGAGCGGAGUCCUCGGAUCCUCACCUGGGUCCUGAGGCCCCGGACUGGGGUCACCUGCGUGGGUCUCUGCAGUUCAGGCCUCUUCUCCAGGACAGCGAGGAGUUCUGGGUGGGGUCCUCAGAGCUGACGGGCGGUGAGGUGAAGAAGGGAGAGCGUUGCGUACCGUGGGGGCUGCACGCGCAGAGCCUGGGAGGUGCGCCGGGGUCGCGAGCAUUCGGAAACUUGGGGGCGGACCUGUGUCUGCAGGGAGCAGAGAGAAUGAGGAGAAGAAGGCACGGCUGCCAUGGCAGCCUGAGCAACCGGGGUUUUUAAUUCUGAGUCUUUGGGAGCCAUGGAGGGUUGUGAACUAAAGGAGAACACGAUCUGAGUGAGGGUCUGAAAAAAUAUUUCAAAGGCAAUGAGUGGAGAAAACAGACUGUUACGGAGUGAUGGGGGUGGACGCAGGGAUACUGGUGAGGAGACUGCUGUAGUAGGCUCCAGGAGGAUUAUGGUGGAUUCUGGACCAGACGGGUUGCUGAAGGGACCUAAGUAAUAAGAAUCUUGGUAGAUCUUAAAGGUAAAGCCAGCAGGAUUUUCUGCUCCAUCAUUUGUGCCUAUGAGCAAAAGUGGGAGUGAAGUAUGAUCCCAAGUUUUUCUUUUACCUGAACAUCUGGAAGAGUUGACAAAGAAAUCUGGUGAGGGAGCAGGUUUCAGGGAAAUAGUAGGAGUUGAAUUUUGGACGUGGUGUUUCUAAAUUGCCACAGAGUGAAGUUGUUACAUGGGCAGUUGGAAUCAUAAGUAGAAAAUUCAUGGGAGGGGACUGACUCAGUGAUGUGUAAAUGGAGACAGGCUGGGGCGUAGACUCAAGCCAAGCCUUAAAUUUAGACGGGAAAUCUUAAGGUUUUACUUUGAGAUGAAGAGAGGGAGGGCUGAGGCUGGAGGCUGGGAAAGUGUGGGUCGGCCUUGGCGAAGCUGCCUGCAGAUAGGAGGGCCAUGGGGUUCCGGGGGUACUUCCAAAGGGAAUGUGUAAGGAAUACACACUGCAUAGGAUGGAUUUGAGGGUGGGACACUGUGUAGAGUCACCAUUCAGAAGACUUGGCGAACUGUUCACUCUAUGUGGAGCCAGAGAAAGGUCAGCCAGACUAGCAGAGAAGCCCAAGCCCAGCAAGAGCAGCUCUCCCAGGAAAAUACAAGUUUAGACUGUAUAGAUUUAACAAAUUAAAUUUAUGCAAGCAAUUAGUUAACCGAAUAAAAUGUCACUAUAACUCUGUGCUCUAAUAAAAAAUAAAUGUUUGUUUUUUGUCAUGCUUUCCUGGCACAGAAUUCCUAAAAUCGUUGUAAUUUCCUCAGUGAAAAGUGUCUUGUGAUAAGUCAUGGACCGCAUAACAACAGUGUUGACCACAUCAGUGACGGUGGUCCCAUAAGAUUAUGAUACCAUAUUUUUACUGUACCUUUUCAUUUUCUUUCUUUCUGAUCAGGAGGCAAACUGCAUUUUCUAAGUUUAUAAAUGUUUAAAUGCACAAAUAAUUAUCACUGUGUUACAGUUGCUGACAGUAUUUAGUAUAGUAACUUGCUGUACAGGUUUGUAGCCUAGGAGCAAUAGGCUAUACCAUUUAGUAGUUGAACAAUGAAUGUCUGAACAGUAGUUCCCCCUUAUCCUCAGAGGAUACCUUUCAAGAACCCCAGCGGAGGCUUGAAACUGCAGAUAGUACCCAACCUAUAUAUACUAUGUUUCUUCCUAGACUACAUACCUGUAAUAAAAUCCAGUUUAUAAAUGAGGCAGUAUAGGAGAUGAACAAUAAUAACUGGAAAUAAUAUAGAACAGUUAUACUUUAUAAGUUAAUAAAAGUUAAGUAACUGCAGUUGAGACAAUAAAAAAGCAAAAGUUAAAUUAUAAAAAACAUGUGAAUGUGGUAUCUCUCUAAAUAUCUUACUGUACUAUUCACCCUUGUGAUGAAGAAGGGACUAAACUCGAUAGAGUGAGAUUUCCUCACACUACUUACAAUGGUGCACUGUUGGCCAGCGCAGUGGCUCACACCUGUAAUCCCAGCACUUUGGGAGGCUGAGGCAGGCAGAUCACAAGGUCAGGAGAUCGAGACCAUCCUGGCUAACAUGGUGAAACCCCGUCUCUACUAAAAAUACAAAAAAUUAGCCAGGUGUGGUAGUGGGCGCCCGUAGUCCCAGCUACUCCGGAGGCUGAGGCAGGAGAAUGGUGUGAAGCUGGGAGGCAGAGCUUGCAGUGAGCCGAGAUUGCACCACUACACUCCAGCCUGGGCGACAGAGCGAGGCUCCGUCUCCAAAAAUAAAUAAAUAAAAUAAAUAAAUAAAUAAAUAAAUAAAGGAUGGUGCACUAUUUAAAACAUGAAUUGUUUAUUUCUGGAAUUUUAAUAUUACUAUUUUCAGACUGAAGUUGAAAUUUAAUACUUAUAAUUUUCACACUGAAGUUGAGUGUGGGUAACUGAAACUGCAAAUAGCAAAACAGCUGAUAAGGGAAGACUUCUAUACUUGAGUUUUAUGAGAUGGCUUAGGGUGAGCAGACAAGGUGGAGUCUCUAGAUAGCCUCAGAGUGGAGUCAGUCACCAGAAAAAUCAAGUGAUUAUAGAAUUUGAACUUUGAGCCCCACCUCUGGCAUCCAGGGAGGGGAGCAGAGAUCUGGAGAUUAGGUUAUAUAAAAUCUUGAACAAUGAGUUCUAGAAGCUUCAAGGUUGUGAACACUUGGAAGUGCUGGGAGAGUGACGUAAGAGAGCGUGGAAGUACUCUGCCUUACCCCCUCUCCCAGUACCUUGCCAUAUGCAUCGCUUCCAUUUGGCUGUUCCUGAGUUACAUCCAUUAUCAUAAACUGGUAAACAUAAGUAAAAUAUUUUCCUGAGUUCUGUAAGUGGUUCUAGCAAAUUAUUGAACGUAAGGAGAGAGGUCAUGGCAGCCCCCAAAUGUGUAGCCAAGUGGAGAAAAUUACAGUGGUCUGGACAUUGGCUUGCAAUUGCCAUAUGAAGUGAGGGCAGUUUUGUACGACUGAGCCCUUAAACCUGUUGGUUUAGCUGCAACUCCAGGUAGUUAGUGUUAGAAUAGGAUUGAAUUGUAGGACACCUAGUUGGUAUCAGAAUCAGAGAAUGGUGUGGGAAAAGACACUACAUAUUUAUUAUCAAAGAAGCACAGAAGCCUCUCAUAAUUUGAAAAGAUACCACAUUCACAUAAAGACUUAAAUGGCAAGUAAGAAACACCAGAGUUUUAAAAAAUGUUUACAGAAAUCUUAAUGCAAUAGUCAGUACUAGCUAAAUCUUAGCAUUGGACACGUAUGAAUGAGUUUGAUGCCUACGAUGGCACUACGAGAUAGCCACCAUUAAGUGUUUCCAUUUUACAGAUGAAGGCAACCUCAGAGAGGUUAGGUCUUUGUCUAGUGUCACACAGUUGGCAAGAGCAACUUACCCUUUGUAAAUGCCACCUUGAACACCUGUAUUUCAUAGCCUCCCUCUUCCUACAGAUUCCCAUGGUAACAGAAGAGUUUGUGAAACCAUCACAGGGCCAUGUGACCUUUGAGGAUAUUGCUGUGUACUUCUCCCAGGAGGAGUGGGGCCUCCUUGAUGAAGCUCAAAGGUGCCUGUAUCAUGAUGUGAUGCUGGAGAACUUUUCGCUUAUGGCCUCAGUAGGUUGUUUGCAUGGAAUAGAGGCUGAGGAGGCCCCUUCUGAGCAGACUCUUUCUGCGCAAGGAGUGUCACAGGCCAGGACUCCAAAGCUAGGUCCUUCCAUCCCAAAUGCUCAUUCUUGUGAGAUGUGUAUCCUGGUCAUGAAAGACAUUUUGUACCUCAGUGAGCAUCAGGGGACACUUCCCUGGCAGAAACCUUAUACGUCUGUGGCCAGUGGGAAAUGGUUUUCAUUUGGUUCUAACCUGCAACAGCACCAGAACCAGGACAGUGGAGAGAAACACAUCAGAAAGGAGGAGAGCAGUGCCUUGCUUCUGAAUAGCUGCAAAAUUCCUCUGUCAGACAAUCUUUUCCCAUGCAAAGAUGUUGAGAAGGAUUUUCCAACCAUCCUGGGCCUUCUCCAACACCAGACCACCCACAGCAGACAAGAGUAUGCACAUAGAAGCAGGGAGACCUUUCAACAAAGACGUUACAAAUGUGAGCAAGUUUUCAAUGAGAAAGUUCAUGUUACUGAGCAUCAGAGAGUCCACACUGGAGAAAAAGCUUAUAAGCGUAGGGAAUAUGGGAAAUCCUUGAACUCUAAAUACUUAUUUGUUGAACACCAGAGAACCCAUAAUGCAGAAAAGCCUUAUGUGUGCAAUAUAUGUGGGAAAUCAUUCCUCCAUAAACAAACACUCGUUGGGCACCAGCAGAGAAUUCACACUAGAGAAAGGUCUUAUGUGUGCAUCGAAUGUGGGAAAUCCUUGAGCUCCAAAUACUCACUUGUGGAACACCAGAGAACCCAUAAUGGAGAAAAGCCUUAUGUGUGCAAUGUAUGUGGGAAAUCAUUCCGCCACAAACAAACAUUUGUUGGCCAUCAGCAGAGAAUCCACACUGGAGAGAGGCCUUAUGUGUGUAUGGAAUGUGGGAAAUCUUUUAUUCAUUCCUAUGACCGCAUUCGACACCAGAGAGUUCACACUGGAGAAGGGGCUUAUCAGUGCAGUGAAUGUGGGAAAUCCUUCAUAUACAAACAGUCACUUCUUGAUCACCAUAGAAUCCACACGGGAGAAAGGCCUUAUGAGUGCAAAGAAUGUGGGAAGGCCUUCAUUCACAAAAAAAGACUUCUUGAGCACCAGAGAAUUCAUACUGGAGAAAAGCCUUAUGUGUGCAUCAUAUGUGGGAAAUCAUUUAUCCGCUCGUCUGACUACAUGCGACACCAGAGAAUUCACACUGGAGAAAGGGCUUAUGAAUGCAGUGACUGUGGGAAAGCCUUCAUCUCCAAACAAACACUUCUUAAGCAUCACAAAAUCCACACUAGAGAAAGGCCUUAUGAAUGCAGUGAAUGUGGAAAAGGCUUCUACCUUGAGGUUAAACUUCUUCAGCACCAAAGAAUCCAUACUAGAGAACAACUUUGUGAGUGCAAUGAAUGUGGAAAAGUCUUCAGCCACCAAAAAAGACUUCUUGAGCACCAGAAAGUUCACACUGGCGAAAAGCCCUGUGAGUGCAGUGAAUGUGGGAAAUGCUUUAGACACCGCACCAGCCUCAUUCAACACCAGAAAGUUCACAGUGGAGAGAGGCCUUAUAACUGCACUGCAUGUGAGAAGGCCUUUAUCUAUAAAAACAAACUUGUUGAGCAUCAGCGAAUCCACACCGGAGAAAAGCCGUAUGAAUGUGGUAAAUGUGGGAAAGCCUUCAACAAAAGAUAUUCCCUUGUCAGGCACCAGAAGGUACAUAUAACAGAAGAGCCCUAGCAAUUGUUGGGAUGUGUAAUUGUCUUAUUCACUGUAGGACACCAGAGAGCUGAUUUUUCAAGGGAUCCAACAGACAGAAAUUCACCCUCAUACAUCUGCAUAUCACUAGUUGAAAGAUUCACUACAAGGUCCAAGUACUUGGGAAGCUUUCUAGAGAUUACUUGUACUUUCUAAUCUGCCCAGUGUUACAACAGACACUACCAUGUGGCAUAUCCUCACCGUUUUCAUCAGUCACUCACAUGUGCUCAAGGAAUGCAGACCACUGUGCUUACCAAAUUCUGAAGGGAAUAAUAUAAUAAAAGCCUGUUGAGGGUCCUCUUCCAUCUUGCUGAACUGUUCGAGGCAAAGACAAAACCCAACUUUGACCAAGAAGAGCAAUCUGGAUUCUUGUAGCCCAUGGAGGUUUACCUUCUUCAUAGGUUUUUUUUUUUUUUAUGUGAUUGCCAUAGUGGGAUAUUCCCUCUCCCACAUUACCCAAGAGGGAAAUGGGCUGUCUUACCAUGUGCUGAUGUAUGUGCUCUGCCAGUGUGAAGGGUGAACAGCUCCAACUUUAUGUCCCCCCAGGGACAUAGUAUGAGAUCGGAAAAUAGUUCUUAGUCCUGUUUGUCUUAAUUUUUAUUGGUUUCCAAGGUCUCCUAGGAAGGAGAGCAGAGCUGUGUGGUCCUAAUCAUGGUGUCGAUGCCAGAUUUAUUUGUAGGUCCAGAGGUCUCCCUGAGAAGAGGCAUUUGUGACAAACUCAAGUGCUGGGACCUGCAUGAAUUGUUUAUUUGCAGUGAUGCUUCAUAUUUCCCAGCACUGUUCAUGGUAUCUUAUUUCCCAGGUCCUUCAUUGUAGCCAUGGGCACUGAAGGACUGAAUUGGUAGGUAGGUCACUGGUUGUAAGACCUACUGGGGCCAGGUAAGAACAGUAAUUGGCCCAGACAGGUAGGUGUGAUAAACAGAGUAGAAAAGAUUGUGGCCAAGAAGAGUGAAUGUGUCCCAUCCAAAGGUGCAUCCAGAUAUGUCUGUGUUACUAUGGCUUCAUGGUUUGGGGGUAUAUAGAAAUUCUCAGGACCUCAGACCUUUGAUUCUCCUUUAGCAACACACAUCGUCAGCAUAAGGCAUCUAAAGAUUUUGUGGACUCAUAACUUAUGUACUGUUUUUGAGAUGAUUGCUGCACGGGCAGGAAAGCAGGAUUUGAGAGAACAUACACCUUGCCUUCCAGAUAUGUGGUUUUUGUGAUUCACCCAGAUCUGUUGUGCCAGUUAGGAAUUAUCUUUAUUACUUCCCGUUUAUUGCCACUGCUGAGAAGGCUGUCCUUCCUAACUUGUGAGGAGAUGAAUCCUUAAUAAUAAGUAAAUCUUGUGUUAUCCUAUAGUCUGGUUUUCCAAAAGGAGAGGUAGAUGCAUAUUUUUGUGUGGAACCAUUUAUCUUAAAACAUUGAGGUGCAGUUUUCAUACACAAAACCUUCUAUCUUUUUAAGAACUGUCUGUAUGGUUUAUUGCCCAGUUAAUGGGUUUUGAUAGUCAUGUUAUCUCAGUAAGUGUCUUGUCUUAGAAAUAUGUGUGUAUAGGCUGGGUGCGGUGGCUCAUGCCUGUAAUCCCAGCACUUUGGGAGGCCAAGGCAGGUGGAUCACCUGAGGUCAGGAGUUUGAGACCAGCCUGACCAACAUGGUGAAAUCCAGUCUCUACUUAAAAUACAAAAAUUAGCCAGGCGUGGUGGCGUGCAUUUGUAAUCCCAGCUACACAGGAGGCUGAGGCAGGAGAAUUGCUUGAACCUGGGGGGCGGAGGUUGCAAUGAGCCAAGGUCGCGCCAUUGCACUCCAGCCUGGGCGACAGAGUGACACUUCUCAAAAAACAAAAACAAAAACAAAAAGAACAGAUAAGAAAUACGUGUGUAUAUAUUCUAUUUUGUGUGUUUUCAUUCACCUUAUUUCAUUCAGUCUUCCAAAUGAAAUGUUCUUAAUUUUGA